GAUUAGUUACUGAUCCUCUUUGCAUUUGUAAAGCUUUGGAGAUAUUGAAUCAUGUUACCAUUUCUGUUUUUUUCCACCCUGUUUUCUUCCAUAUUUACUGAAGCUCAGAAGCAGUAUUGGGUCUGCAACUCAUCCGAUGCAAGUAUUUCAUACACCUACUGUGAUAAAAUGCAAUACCCAAUUUCAAUUAAUGUUAACCCCUGUAUAGAAUUGAAAAGAUCCAAAGGAUUAUUGCACAUUUUCUACAUUCCAAGGAGAGAUUUAAAGCAAUUAUAUUUCAAUCUCUAUAUAACUGUCAACACCAUGAAUCUUCCAAAGCGCAAAGAAGUUAUUUGCCGAGGAUCUGAUGACGAUUACUCUUUUUGCAGAGCUCUGAAGGGAGAGACUGUGAAUACAACAAUAUCAUUCUCCUUCAAGGGAAUAAAAUUUUCUAAGUCUGUUACCCAGGCUGGAGUGCAGUGGCACGAUCUCUGCUCACUGCAACCUCCACCCGCCAACCCCCACCCCAAGCAAUCCUCCUGCCUUAGCCUCCUGACUAGCUGGGACUACAUGUCCAUGCCACAAUGCCAGCUAAUGUUUUGUACUUUUGGAAGAGACGCGGUUUCACCAUGUUGCCCAGGUUGGUCUUGAAUUCCUGAGCUCAAGCGAUCCACUCCGCUUAGCCUCCCAAAGUGCUGGGAUUACAAGUAUGGGCAGUUGUGCCCAGCUGACAAUUUCAUGAAUAGCAGUUCGAGAUUAAGAUGUUCAGGGUUUUUUCUUUCACUUUUAUUUAGAAUUAGCUUUUUUUUUUUUUUUUUAACUGAGUCUUGCUCUGUUGCCCAGGCUGGAGUGAAGUGUGUUCUGGACUCACUGCAACUUCCGCCUCCCAGGUUCAGGUGAUUCUGUGCCUCAACCACCCGAGUAGCUGGGAUUACAGGCACAUGCCACUAUGCCCAGCUAAUUUUUUUAUUUUUAGUAGAGAUGGGGUUUCACCAUGUUGCCCAGGCUGGUCUCAAACUCCUGGCCUCAUGUGAUCCACCCACCUUUGUUCCUGGACCAAACUGAGGGUCGGGCUGCCAUUUCUCGCAGCCCAAUAGCAAGAUGCAGAUGAACUGGGGAGGAAGAGAGCUUUUAUUUCUGUAACUGGUUACAGGGAGAAGGUCUGGAAAUUAUCGCCAGACCAACUCAAAAUUACAAAGUUUUCAGAGCUUAUAUACAUUCUAAGGUAUAUGUCUAUGUGUAAGUGUGCAUUCAUCUGAAGACACAAGUGAUUAACUUCUUUUAAUCUAUAAUUAAGGUCUGAGUCCUGAAGACCUUCAUCUGGAGCCUCAGGAACUUUACUUAAUCUAAAUGGGUCUGGGUGCUGGGGUGAUUACCUUUAUCUUGUCUCCUGCUAAAUCAUGGAGGUUUGAGGAGUUCCUUCAGACCCCCAGUAAACUUGGUUGUGGAAGCCUGGGGAGUUUCUUCGGACCCACAAUAAAACUCGAUUGAUCCUAAAUGGGUCCUAUUAAGAAUUUCUUAGUUAUUUUGUUAUGGUUUAAGAAAGCCUUAAAGGAAGGGCCUGGGCAAAACUCCUGAUGGGCUUUUGUUACAUCCCAUCCUUUGCAUAAGGGCGCUGGCUUUAAAUAUUUAACUUAACCACUCAGUACUGAAACAGUUGUUAGUGAGACCUGGCCUUGGCCUCCCAAACUGCUGGGAUUAUAGGUGUGAGCCACCACACCCAGCCUUAGUAUUAGGUCUUUUGGUAUUUUUUCUUUCUGUAGACUAUGGAAAAAUUGCACAAAACAUAGCAUUUUUUUCCGCUUCAUUUUUUUUUCCCUCUAACAUACAUGGGCAAAAGUAAUUUGAAUGCAAGUGCUCAUUACUAAUCUGUUGAACAGUCUUCAGAUGAAAGCACUGGAUGACCAUUGUGUAUAAGCCAGUAAAUCUCUAUAACUAUUCAUGUAAAUAUAAUGUGAACAUUGUUUAGGAGAAUAAAAAUCACAUAAAUUACAGACUUUUUUUGUUCAAGAUUUUUUUGGGAACUUAGUCUGGUCAUCCAUGCCUUUGUAAAAAUAAUUGCUGCCUCAAUGAAUAAUACCAUUGUGAUUCUAGAUAUUUGCGUGACAUAUCUAGUAAUGAGAUUUUAUGCAUUUUACUUAUGGUGACCAUUUUAAAAUAAAAUUUAAUAAUGCA